GAGUUCUCCUCUAUGGCUUCUACUUAUAAGUCCAUUGAUAUCCCUGGCUCAACAGAGAAUAGAAGAUGAAACAGCAAAUCUACCACUUGAUUCUGAUGAACAAAUCAUGCCGACAUUCAAUGGCUCAGUCUUCAUGCCCUCUGCGUUUAUACUAAUUGGGAUUCCUGGUCUGGAGUCAGUGCAGUGUUGGAUUGGGAUUCCUUUCUCUGCCAUGUAUCUUAUUGGUGUGAUUGGAAAUUCCCUAAUUUUAGUUAUAAUCAAAUAUGAAAACAGCCUCCAUAUACCCAUGUACAUUUUUUUGGCCAUGUUGGCAGCCACAGACAUUGCACUUAACACCUGCAUUCUUCCCAAAAUGUUAGGCAUCUUCUGGUUUCAUUUGCCAGAGAUUUCUUUUGAUGCCUGUCUUUUUCAAAUGUGGCUUAUUCACUCAUUCCAGGCAAUUGAAUCGGGUAUCCUUCUGGCAAUGGCCCUGGAUCGCUAUGUGGCCAUCUGUAUCCCCUUGAGACAUGCCACCAUCUUUUCCCAGCAGUUCUUAACUCAUAUUGGACUUGGGGUGACACUCAGGGCUGCCAUUCUUAUAAUACCUUCCUUAGGGCUCAUCAAAUGCUGUCUGAAACACUAUCGAACUACAGUCAUCUCUCACUCUUACUGUGAGCACAUGGCCAUCGUGAAGCUGGCUACUGAAGAUAUCCGAGUCAACAAGAUAUAUGGCCUAUUUGUUGCCUUUGCAAUCCUAGGGUUUGACAUAAUAUUUAUAACCUUGUCCUAUGUCCAAAUUUUUAUCACUGUCUUUCAGCUGCCCCAGAAGGAGGCACGAUUCAAGGCCUUUAAUACAUGCAUUGCCCACAUUUGUGUCUUCCUACAGUUCUACCUUCUUGCCUUCUUCUCUUUCUUCACACACAGGUUUGGUUCACACAUACCACCAUAUAUUCAUAUCCUCUUGUCAAAUCUUUACCUGUUAGUCCCACCUUUUCUCAACCCUAUUGUCUAUGGAGUGAAGACCAAGCAAAUUCGUGACCAUAUUGUGAAAGUGUUUUUCUUCAAAAAAGUAACUUGAUCGUUAGUGACUCCUAUAGAGAUUUAGGGUUGGUUCUAAGUAAAAACCUAAAUAUAAUGAAAGUCACAGAUCAAUAUUCUCAAACUACUAGCUCAACACAUACCUGUAAUUCUAGCUAUGUCUCACUUUUUAGUAUUUGCUUUGAAUCUAUAUUUUGAUAAAUUUGGAAUCAUUUAUCUGUGUCUUAUUUACUUUAUCUGAAAUACUUAUCAAUAUAAAAAUAAUAUGAAAUCAGUAAUACCGAUAUCUACAACAUAAAACUUAUGUAAUGCAACCAAUGACUAUAAACACUAAGGAAUUUACACAGGAGAGAAUGCAAAAAAAAUUGAAAAAUAUUAAACAUAUUCACAAAUAUCAUUUUCAGGAAAAUAAAAUCAGUGAUCUGGGCUUACAUAUCAAAUAUCCUUCUAGAACCACACAAUUUUAUUGAUUUUUACCUAACUUGAGUUUUACUCAAAUUUGGAAGUUUAAGUUCUAAAAUUGAACAUACAAAUUCUGUUACCCACUGAAAGCAUCUUGAGUACAGAAACUAUCUUAUUUACCCUUUAUCAGGAAAACAGUGGACAAUGCCUGAGAAUUCUUAGAAUCUAAGUAAAAAUGACAUUGAAUAAUGAACAGAGUAAACAUUUUCUUUGUGUCAAUUAAUGGUAUUCAAAAGCCACAAAUUUGGAGGCUCUAAGUAAUAUGCAAUCUUACCAUACAGAAAACCAUGCUAGAGAUUUUAUUCCAAUAUUAUCAGGGUAAAAGAAAGGUGAAGACUUGAAAUAAUCAUUAUGCAAACCUGAAAUAAUAUAUUAGCUAAACACAGAACUGGCAUAUAAGAAACCACCUCCUGAAUAAGGACUUUAGUCAAGACUUAGAACCAAACAAAUUUUUUUUUCCUUAAGAAUCAAGUUGACAGAGUCAUCUGAAUCACUAAUUUUGAAAAGAUGCAUGGUCAAAGAAAGAAAUAAUAUGGUAAAACGUUCUGAUGUAAAAAAUCAUAUCAUUCAAGAGGCAGACAUAGAUACAUACAAUUUUGGGGAAAAAUCUUGUCAAUAAUGUAGAAAUGACUUUGAGUCAUAAUUUUUUUAAUAAAGUUUAUGUAAACAUUAUAUUUAGAAAGAAUCAAAAAUACAUGACAAAAGAUAAAACAACAUGUUAGUUGAUAGGCAGACAUAUUAAAAAUUGUUGAAUUAGAUAAGCAAAACUUAAUAAUGAAAUAACCAUUUUAAUUCUGGAUUAGAGCAUUAAAUAUUUCAGUGGUUGUGCCAUUAAUAACGCAGAAUGAAUAAUUAAUGAGGAGUCAUUCUCCCAAAAGAAAAAAAAAUCAUAAAUAUAUGAAUUCUUUCAGAAAAGUUAGUAUACAUGAAGGAUAAAGAAUGAAGAUAAUAAGUAAGUGAUACUCCUAAAUAAGAAACCAAAACAAACAAUAUGAUGAUAACUACAGAUUAAUCAUGAGUGAAUGAAAAAACUGUAUUUCAAAGUAUCUGGUAUAAAAAUGCACCAAAUUAUAUAAAUGAAAAUAGACAAAACACCCAUAUUGGAAAAAAAUCAACAGAAAAUAAAAAUUUCAACAUAGGUCUAUCAGAAAAAAACACAUUACAUAUCCUAAAAGACAUAUUUUUUUUUCAUUCUCUGGAGUAUGAGGGAAGACAAACAACAAAGAUCUUAAAAAUGCACAUUAUCUAAUGGAAAAAAAUUAAAUGAAAAAUUUGUGUCAUAAUUAGACUGUGGGUUGGCAUUUCAAGCCAUUUAAACCUGUAAUUAAUAAAAAGAACAAUUACAGUGCAUAAUAAUAUUACUAGUUUCUGAAACAAUGUUGUCCCUGUCCAGUGUUCUCUGCUAAAGAAACCCCAGCUGAAGCAAUUUCCACAUGGAGUACAGCACCUGGUCCAGCUGAUUUCAGCUAGGUCCCAGUCAGCACACAGAUCUGUUUGACUUCUUGGUUGCUUUUUGGUCUUCUUUACAGGUCAAAUUUGUUCCAUGCUGAAGAUCUGGGUUCAUAUUACCUUUUUUUAAGGUAUAAAAAAAGACCUGGCCUCAAAAUGAGGUUGUACACGUAGUUUCUGAGAGUCUGCUCCAUUGCUCUUCAAUUGAGGGCUCUGGCUAAUUGGAUGCAGAAUCCGAGAUAAAGGACAGCCACCUACAGCAGCUAGAGGGCUGAGAUAUGAGUCAGACUGAUAUGCCCUGACUAUGAUGCAAUGAACAUCUUAAAAAGAGAAAUUUAUUCCAAGAAUAAAUUGUUUGAGGGCUCGAAGGGAUUGCCUUAAGUUAAAGAUGGAUAAAUAGGUAUCCUAGCUAGGAAUCAAAAAGGUCUGAGUUUCUCCAUUACCCUUCCUUUAACAUUCUACAUACUCCUGGGCAUGUUAUUUCCUCUUCUCUACAAUGGGGCUAACAAUACGAGCCUCAGAGACUUGUGAGGAAUAUGUGAGAAAAGGCUCACCAAGCAUGUAGCACAGAUCCAGGCUAAAACACACCUUAAACAUGUAGGCCAAGGUGUACAUACUCUGAGAAUUAAGAUGCAGAGAAAAAUGAUUUCAGGAUUAAGUGCAAAGAGACGGAAAUGAAUGGAGCAGAGUGCCGGGAUAGCUGUGUGGCUGAUGAUCCUCUAGCUGGAGCUAGGUCAGUGUCUUUGGGCAGAGCUGUGUGUAACAUUCUCAGAAGCAUGCUGAGACAACAGAAUACCUUGGUGAUCUUUAUUCAAUUGUUUAUUUUUACUGAGAUGGAAUUCACAUGCCAUAAUAUUUGCAAUUUUAAAGUAUGCAAUUUGAUGAUUUUUAGUGUAUUAUAAAGGCUGUGCAACCAUCAUCACUACCUAAUUGAAAAUACUUUCGUCAUCCUAAAAAAAAAUCUAUAUACAUUAGUAGUCACAUCCCAUUACUUCUGCUCCCCCCAUCUCCAGUCUUAGCAACUGCUAAUCUCUUUUCUGUUUCA